AGUCAGCCAGGAGGCUCCAAACUGUUAGCGACAAAAACGCAGCUCUCGGUCACUCCCACUACCCUCCCACCCGCACUCCAGGCAUAUUUUGGAGGCGGCAGCAGCGGUGGCAGGAUGUGAGGCGAGCCUGGAGCUCAUUUCCAGGCGCCCUUCCCUCUUCGGAACUAAGGGAGACUUGUGGGCUUUUGCACACUGGCUGUAGGGUUCCCGGGAAAGACUGGAGCAGCGAACAGGAGGGAGAGAGGUGGACAGGCAGAGUCUGCACCUGCCGCCUGCACCUCCGUUAGGGCGACAGGGCAGCUGGUGUUUCGCUCCUGGAGUGUGCCUACCUCGCAAGGGGGGCGAGGGCCACAGGCUGAGGCGCCCGCGUCCCGGAGUGCACCGCUUGGCCGAGGCAAGGUGUUGCUGGGGCAAGGCUGCUCCGAAGCGAAGUCGCGCAAAAGGAAGAGUCUGGGAGGCAGGCGACUUAGGAGAGUCUAGUCACUGAGAGACAGAGGCAGCAUCUGCCAUUCUAACUACGGAGCUGAGUAAUUUAGAAACCCUCCUUAACUCUCCCUUUCCAGCUCUCCCCAAAGUCCACAGAAGCUCUGCUGAACUCUAGAAAUCUUCCCUGGCUGGGGGGAAGUUUACUAGUAUCCUCUUUGGCUAAGACAGGGAGUGGAAAAAACAGGCGGGGCUGUACUGUCCGCUGUUUGGGGAGACGCGGUCUUCCUCGCGCCCCCUUCAGCCACUCCGACUGCCUGGGAAGUCCCAGCCCGCGCUCUCCGGAACCCGGCUCGCCGUCUCGCCCUGGACAUGGAACUACGCAUCUGAGACCUGCUGGACGUUUUGCUGGCCGUUUUGCAAGACUCAGCUGUCAAGAAAAGUGAAGGAUGAAGCCACCAUUUCUUUUGGCCCUUGUGGUCUGUUCUGUAGUCAGCACAAAUCUGAAGAUGGUGUCAAAGAGAAAUUCUGUGGAUGGCUGCAUUGACUGGUCAGUGGAUCUCAAGACAUACAUGGCUUUGGCAGGUGAACCAGUCCGAGUGAAAUGUGCCCUUUUCUACAGUUAUAUUCGUACCAACUAUAGCACGGCCCAGAGCACUGGGCUCAGGCUUAUGUGGUACAAAAACAAAGGUGAUUUGGAAGAGCCCAUCAUCUUUUCAGAGGUCAGGAUGAGCAAAGAGGAAGAUUCAAUAUGGUUUCACUCAGCUGAGGCACAAGACAGUGGAUUCUACACUUGUGUUUUAAGAAACUCAACAUAUUGCAUGAAGGUGUCAAUGUCCUUGACUGUUGCAGAGAAUGAAUCAGGCCUGUGCUACAACAGCAGGAUCCGCUAUUUAGAAAAAUCUGAAGUCACUAAAAGAAAGGAGAUCUCCUGUCCAGACAUGGAUGACUUUAAAAAGUCCGAUCAGGAGCCUGAUGUUGUGUGGUAUAAGGAAUGCAAGCCAAAAAUGUGGAGAAGCAUAAUAAUACAGAAAGGAAAUGCUCUUCUGAUCCAAGAAGUUCAAGAAGAAGAUGGAGGAAAUUACACAUGUGAACUUAAAUAUGAAGGAAAACUUGUAAGACGAACAACUGAAUUGAAAGUUACAGCUUUACUCACAGACAAGCCUCCCAAGCCAUUGUUCCCCAUGGAGAAUCAGCCAAGUGUUAUAGAUGUCCAGCUGGGUAAGCCUCUGAACAUCCCCUGCAAAGCAUUCUUCGGAUUCAGUGGAGAGUCUGGGCCAAUGAUCUACUGGAUGAAAGGAGAAAAGUUUAUUGAAGAACUGGCAGGUCACAUUAGAGAAGGUGAAAUAAGGCUUCUCAAAGAGCAUCUUGGAGAAAAAGAAGUUGAAUUGGCACUCAUCUUUGACUCAGUUGUGGAAGCUGACCUGGCGAAUUAUACCUGCCAUGUUGAAAACCGAAAUGGACGGAAACAUGCCAGUGUUUUGCUGCGUAAAAAGGAUUUAAUCUAUAAAAUUGAGCUUGCAGGGGGCCUGGGAGCAAUCUUCCUCCUCCUUGUACUGCUGGUGGUCAUUUACAAAUGCUACAACAUUGAAUUGAUGCUCUUCUACAGGCAGCACUUUGGAGCUGAUGAAACUAAUGAUGACAACAAGGAAUAUGAUGCCUAUCUCUCUUACACAAAAGUGGACCAAGAUACUUUAGACUGUGACAAUCCUGAAGAAGAGCAGUUUGCUCUUGAAGUACUGCCAGAUGUCCUGGAAAAACACUAUGGAUAUAAACUCUUCAUCCCAGAAAGAGACCUGAUUCCAAGUGGAACAUACAUGGAAGAUCUCACAAGAUAUGUUGAACAAAGCAGAAGACUUAUUAUCGUGCUAACUCCAGACUAUAUUCUCAGACGGGGAUGGAGUAUUUUCGAACUGGAAAGCAGACUCCAUAACAUGCUAGUCAGUGGAGAAAUCAAAGUGAUUUUGAUUGAGUGUACAGAAUUAAAAGGGAAAGUGAAUUGCCAGGAAGUGGAAUCACUAAAGCGUAGCAUCAAACUUCUGUCCCUGAUCAAGUGGAAGGGAUCCAAAAGCAGCAAAUUAAAUUCUAAGUUUUGGAAGCACUUAGUAUAUGAAAUGCCCAUCAAGAAAAAAGAAAUGCUACCUCGGUGCCAUGUUCUGGACUCCGCAGAACAAGGACUUUUUGGAGAACUCCAGCCUAUACCCUCUAUUGCCAUGACCAGUACUUCAGCCACUCUGGUGUCAUCUCAGGCUGAUCUCCCUGAAUUCCACCCUUCAGAUUCAAUGCAAAUCAGGCACUGUUGCAGAGGUUAUAAACAUGAGAUACCAGCCACGACCUUGCCAGUACCUUCCUUAGGCAACCACCAUACUUAUUGUAACCUGCCUCUGACGCUACUCAACGGACAGCUACCCCUUAAUAACACCCUGAAAGAUACCCAGGAAUUUCACAGGAACAGUUCUUUGCUGCCUUUAUCCUCCAAAGAGCUUAGCUUUACCAGUGAUAUUUGGUAGUGAAAAAUCUGAAUUCCUCUGAACAGCUAGAUAAGCAUAGAGAAUUUCUGUUAUACCAAGCAUAAAGUACACCUAAUAACGUUGUGUUAAAAAAGUGUUUGAAGAAAAAGGUACAAAAAUGGCUUUUAUACUUAAAUAUUUUUGUUUACAUUUCCAGAAUAGUGGGGG